AAACCUUCCAAACCCACCUUCCUGGAAAUCCACCCAGAACCUCCACCCUCUGACACCAUGGUCAACUCCUGUUGUGGCUCUGUGUGCUCUGACCAGGGCUGUGGCCUAGAGAACUGCUGCCGUCCCAGCUGCUGCCAGACCACCUGCUGCAGGACCACCUGCUGCCGCCCCAGCUGCUGUGUGUCCAGCUGCUGCAGACCGCAGUGCUGCCAGUCUGUGUGCUGCCAGCCCACCUGCUGCAGCCCCAGCUGCUGCCAGACCACUUGCUGCAGGACCACCUGCUGCCGUCCCAGCUGCUGUGUGUCCAGCUGCUUCAGACCCCAGUGCUGCCAGUCUGUGUACUGCCAGCCCACCUGCUGCCGCCCCAGCUGUGGCCAGACCACCUGCUGCAGGACCACCUGCUACCGCCCCAGCUGCUGUGUGUCCACCUGCUGCCGCCCAACCUGCUCUAGUGGCUCUUGCUGCUGAUGCCCUCACCUAUACUCACCUGCCUUUAUUAACCAGCAUUCUUGAUAUGAUCCACCUGUGAACUGAAUCAUGCAAGGCCAAUUGGACAACCUCAGUUCCAACCAAUUCUUGGAUUGAGUUUGGCCUCCAAAUAUGCUCACCAAACACUAUGUUGCUACCCUCUACCAAAUGAAUACAAGUUUGAAUUUUCUCUGAAAUAUGUCAACCCCAUGUUCCCUGAAUUGAAAUAUUUGCUCUCUACCAUAAUUUAUCACAUGGAGCUAUUCCUCUAUCUUAAAUAAAUUUUAAUUUUUGAGGCAUACAAAUAA